GUAUUCUAGAUUGACGCCUUUUGCUGGAAGAGCGCUGCUGGGGUUAGGAUUCUGCGCGGCGAGGCAAGAUGCUCAAGUCCAAGACGUUCUUAAAAAAGACCCGGGCGGGCGGCGUGAUGAAGAUCGUGCGCGAGCACUACCUGCGAGACGACAUCGGCUGCGGUGCGCCCGGGUGCGCAGCGUGUGGAGGGGCGCACGAGGGGCCGGCCCUGGAGCCGCAGCCCCAGGACCCGGCGAGCAGCGUCUGCCCGCAACCGCACUACUUGCUGCCCGACACUAAUGUGUUACUGCACCAGAUUGUAAGUGCCUGGAGGCCGGGGACCUGGGCUUCUGUGGCCUCCAGCCUGCGACUCCCAGGCAGCUUAUUGAUGUUCUUGAGGACCCUGCCAUCAGGAAUGUAAUUGUGCUACAAACAGUUCUUCAAGAAGUGAGAAAUCGCAGUGCCCCCGUAUAUAAACGCAUCCGAGAUGUGACUAAUAACCAAGAGAAGCAUUUCUAUACUUUCACUAAUGAGCACCAUAGAGAAACCUAUGUAGAACAAGAACAGGGAGAAAAUGCUAAUGACAGGAAUGAUAGAGCGAUUCGAGUAGCAGCAAAAUGGUACAAUGAACAUUUGAAAAAAAUGUCAGCAGACAACCAGCUGCAAGUUAUCUUCAUAACAAAUGACAGGAGAAACAAAGAGAAAGCCAUAGAAGAAGGAAUACCAGCUUUCACUUGUGAAGAAUAUGUAAAGAGCCUAACUGCUAACCCCGAACUCAUAGAUCGUCUUGCUUGUUUGUCUGAAGAAGGGAAUGAAAUAGAAAGUGGAAAAAUAAUAUUUUCAGAGCAUCUUCCCUUAAGUAAGCUACAGCAAGGCAUAAAAUCUGGUACAUACCUUCAAGGAACAUUUAGAGCUAGCAGGGAAAAUUACUUGGAAGCUACAGUAUGGAUUCAUGGCGACAAUGAAGAAAAUAAAGAGAUAAUCUUACAGGGACUUAAACAUUUAAACAGAGCUGUUCACGAAGAUAUUGUGGCUGUGGAGCUUCUCCCCAAGAGUCAGUGGGUAGCACCAUCUUCUGUGGUUUUACAUGAUGAAGGUCAAAAUGAAGAAGAUGUGGAGAAAGAAGAAGAGACAGAACGAAUGCUUAAGACUGCUGUAAGCGAGAAAAUGUUGAAGCCUACAGGUAGAGUUGUAGGAAUAAUAAAAAGGAAUUGGAGACCAUAUUGUGGCAUGCUUUCCAAGUCUGACAUUAAGGAGUCAAGAAGACAUCUCUUUACACCUGCUGAUAAGAGAAUCCCUCGAAUUCGCAUAGAAACCAGACAGGCUUCCACAUUAGAAGGACGGAGAAUUAUUGUUGCUAUUGAUGGUUGGCCCAGAAAUUCCAGAUAUCCAAAUGGACACUUUGUGAGAAAUUUAGGUGAUGUUGGAGAGAAAGAGACUGAAACAGAAGUUUUGUUACUUGAACACGAUGUUCCCCAUCAGCCUUUUUCACAGGCUGUUCUUAGUUUUCUGCCAAAGAUGCCCUGGAGCAUUACUGAAAAGGACAUGAAAAACCGAGAAGACCUGAGGCAUCUGUGUAUUUGUAGUGUAGACCCACCAGGAUGUACUGAUAUAGACGAUGCUCUACAUUGUCGAGAACUCGAAAAUGGAAAUUUGGAGGUUGGUGUUCAUAUUGCUGAUGUGAGCCAUUUUAUUAGGCCAGGAAAUGCCUUGGAUCAAGAAUCAGCCAGAAGAGGAACAACUGUGUAUCUUUGUGAAAAGAGGAUUGACAUGGUUCCAGAGUUGCUUAGCUCUAACUUGUGUUCCUUAAAAUGUGACGUGGACAGGCUGGCAUUUUCAUGUAUUUGGGAAAUGAAUCACAAUGCUGAAAUCUUAAAAACGAAGUUUACCAAAAGUGUUAUUAAUUCAAAGGCAUCUCUGACGUAUGCUGAAGCUCAGUUGAGAAUUGAUUCAGCAAACAUGAAUGAUGAUAUUACCACUAGUCUCCGUGGACUGAAUAAACUAGCCAAAAUUCUGAAGAAAAGAAGGAUUGAAAAAGGGGCUUUGACUCUAUCCUCUCCUGAAGUUCGAUUCCACAUGGACAGUGAAACUCACGAUCCUAUAGAUCUGCAGACCAAGGAACUUAGGGAAACAAAUUCCAUGGUUGAAGAAUUUAUGUUACUUGCCAAUAUUUCUGUUGCAAAAAAAAUUCAUGAGGAAUUUUCUGAACAUGCUCUGCUUCGAAAACAUCCUGCUCCACCUCCAUCAAAUUAUGAAAUUCUUGUUAAGGCAGCCAGGUCAAGGAAUUUGGAAAUUAAGACUGAUACAGCCAAGUCUUUGGCUGAGUCUUUGGAUCAGGCCGAAUCUCCUACUUUUCCAUAUCUAAACACUCUGUUGAGAAUAUUAGCCACUCGCUGUAUGAUGCAAGCUGUGUACUUCUGUUCUGGAAUGGAUAAUGAUUUUCAUCACUAUGGCUUAGCGUCUCCAAUAUACACACAUUUUACUUCACCCAUUAGAAGAUACGCAGAUGUCAUUGUUCAUCGGCUUUUGGCUGUGGCUAUUGGGGCUGACUGUACUUAUCCAGAGUUGACAGACAAACACAAGCUUGCAGAUAUAUGUAAAAAUCUAAAUUUCCGGCACAAAAUGGCUCAAUAUGCCCAACGUGCAUCAGUGGCUUUUCAUACCCAGUUAUUCUUCAAAAGCAAAGGAAUAGUAAGUGAAGAAGCCUAUAUUUUAUUUGUAAGAAAGAAUGCCAUUGUGGUAUUAAUUCCAAAGUAUGGUUUAGAAGGGACAGUCUUUUUUGAAGAAAAGGACAAACCAAACCCACAGCUUAUUUAUGAUGAUGAGAUACCCUCACUUAAAAUAGAAGAUACAGUGUUCCAUGUAUUUGAUAAAGUUAAAGUGAAAAUCAUGUUAGACUCAUCUAAUCUUCAACAUCAGAAGAUCCGAAUGUCCCUGGUAGAACCACAGAUACCAGGAAUAAGCAUUCCUACUGAUACUUCAAACAUGGACCUUAAUGGACCAAAGAAAAAGAAGAUGAAGCUUGGAAAAUAGCUAUAUUCAACAAAAAUCUUCAAAGACUGGUUUCUUUUUUAAAAGAAAAAACUUGAAAGAACACUUCUAAGCCUAAGUGUGUGAUACAGUUUGUUACUUUUAAGUACAUUUUAAUAAUUUCAGACAUCUGCAUUUUUAUUGAACAGUUGACUGUAUCUGACCCAUCAUACUACUAUACUUCUGGGUUGAACAGAAUUAUUUAUGCAGAAUAAUUCAAUUGAAUAUCCAUCACUUAAAUACAGUGACAGGACAGCAACUUCAGGGAUCUGUAAAGAUCAUUUAAAUGGAGUGCUCAUCUCAUUGAGGAGCAGAUUAAUUUUGCGUAAGUACUUUGAUUAUUUAAUAUUUGUAAGAAAAAACUUUCAUUUUCCUACAGAGGAAAAUAGAACAAUUUUAGAAGCAAGGAACAAUCUCUUUUCUAAGUCUUGGAAGCUGUCAGUGUUGAGGAUGUAAUCUCCUUUGCCAUCUUUAAUUCACCUAACUUACACUAGGUGUUCUCUUACUGUCUUUAAAAGCUUCCUGUAUUUUAUUAGUGGUCCUUGAAAAACUGUGAAUGUUUGGGAAUUGGUAGAAAGGCAAAAAGUAGGAUAUUUUGACCUGACUGGAAAGAUGGUUGUGUUUUUAUUGCCAGGUAAUAAGUGUGAUCAUUGUUGAACUUCAGCUCCAGUGUCUCUCCAGAAUAAGACAUUGGCAUUCAAAUGUCUAUAUCUUGUUACUUACAAAAUAAAAAACAGAUUAAUUAGUGGCUUUUAAAUUGUAGUUAUAUCAGUGUAUAUACACGAGGGGAACUGUAUAAAGACAUACUAAAGGGAACAGAUUAAAAUAAGUAUUAUUAAUAAAAUUUGGUGUGCCAGACUGACUACUUCCCUUGCUAAUCACAGAGAUUAGUAAUGAUUAAAUUAAUAUCUUCAGGAAUAUUUUGGGAUAGGGUUGCCUUAAAACAUUUUACUUGGCUUAUUCAAUUUCUAAAGCACUUACGUUGUGCCAGGUUCCACUCAAGUAAAUUAUCUCUGCCUUCAAGGAGCUUGCAGUAUAGUGAGAAAAGCCUGCCAAGUAAAUCAGCAGGUAUACUAAAUAGGUAGUCAUUUAGGCACUCAAUAAAUGUUGACUAAUUUUUCCAGUUUCCUAUUACUGAGGAAAACCUCCAUACACUGAGGCAGAAACUUGUGUCAGUUGGAGGAAAAUAGACUUGAGUAGUCUUUGGUCCAGGUAAAAUGGGUCAGUGACACUGAAACAGUAGAGUAGGAGUCAAAAAACCUUUUCUGUGAAGUGCUAGAACAUUUUAGACUUUGUUGGCUAUGGUCUGUAUUGCAACUAUAGUACACAACUCUGCCGUUGAUAGUGUGUAAGGAGCCAUAUACAAUAUGUAAACAAAUCAACAUGACUGUGUUUCAACAAGGCCUGAUUUGUUAAGUUUCAUAUAUAGUCAUAUGUCACUUAAUGACAGGGAUAUGUUCUGAGACAUGUCACUUGGCAAUUUCAUCAUUGUGUGAAAAUCAUGAUGUAGUUACACAAACCUAGAUGGUAUACCCUAUGGUAUCCUAUAUGGGAUAGCCUAUUGCUCCUAACCUACAAACCUGUAUGGCAUAUUACUGUACUGAUUACUGUAGGCGGUUGUAACACAGUGCUAAGUAUUUGUGUAUCUAAACAUAUCUAAACAUAGAAAAGGUACAGUAAAAAUAUAUAUAUAGAUAUAUAUAAGAUAUAAAAUGGUACACCUAUUUAGGACAUUUACCAUGAACAAGUUGGCAGGACUGGAAGCUGGCUCUGGGUGAGUCAGUAAGUGGUUAGUGAAUGUGAAGGCCAUGAUAUUACUGUGCACUACUGUAGACUUUUAUAAACACUAUAUACUUAGGCUACAUAAAGUAAUUUCACUAUGAUGUUACCAUGGCUGUGUCCCCAGGCAAUAGGAAUUUUUCAGCUCCAUUGUAAUCUUACGGGAUCAUCAUCGUAUAUUUGGCCAUUGUUGACCAAAAGUUAUGCAGCACAUCAUUAUAAUUUUGAUGUGUCACAAAACAUUACUCAUUUGAUUUCCCCCACCCCCGCCAACCAUUUAAAAAAGUUUGCCGGCUAGGUGCGGUGGCUCAUGCCUGUAAUCCUAGCAUUUUGGGAGGACGAGGCGGGUGGAUCACUCGAUGUCAGGAGUUUGAGACCAGCCUGGCCAACAUGGUAAAACGCCGUCUCUACUAAAAAUACAAAAACUUAGCUGGGUGUAACGGCGGAUGCCUGUAAUCCCAGCUACUUGGGAGGCUGAGGCAGGAGAAUCGCUUGAACCUGGGAGGCGGAAGUUGCAGUGAGCCGAGAUUGCACCACUGCAGUUCAGCCUGGAUGAUGAGAGUGAGACUCCAUCGCAAAAAAAAAAAAAAAAAAAGAAAAGAAAAUUAGCCAGGUGUGGUGGCAAGUGCCUUUAAUCCCACCUCAGGAGGCUGAGGCAGGAGAAUCGCUUGAACCUGGGAGGCAGAGGUUGCAGUGAGCCAAGAUCGCGCCACUGCACUCCAGCCUGGGUGACAGAACAAGACUGUCUCAAAAAAAAAAAAAGAGAAGAAAAACUGCCUACAGGCCAUAGUUAACCUGCAAUAGAGAAGAAAGGGAAGUAGGGCAGUGCAUGACUGGCCUUAGGUUUUUUCUUUCCAAGUUUAUUUUCUUGUGCUUCAGCUACUAGAAAGGUUUAAUUCAGGGAUAAGUCCCAAUUGAGUAGUUCAAGAUGAUCAGAGACUUUGCUAUUUUCCCCUAAGUUCUAUUCCAUAAUCUAAAAUGUUCUGUUUCUAGUGCCAGUUCUUAUGCUAAGCAGGUUACGUGGAAUAUAUCACUUAACUCAAAAAGCCCUGUUAAGCCAGGACUGUUAUCUCCAUUUAACAGAUGAGAAAAUGGAGGUUUAUGGUCUGUUCUCACACUGCUACGAAGAAAUACCCCAAACUGGGUAAUUAUUAUAAAGGAAAGAGGUUUAAUGGACUCAGUUCCGCAUUGCUGGUGAGGCCUCAGGACACUUACACAAUCAUGGCAGAAAAAGGAGAAGCAGGCACCUUUUUCACAGGGCGGCAGGAUGAAAAUGACUGCCAGCAGUGGAAAUGCCAGACGCUUAUAAAACCUUCAGAUCUCAUGAGACCGGCUCACUAUCACAGGAACAGCAUGGAGGAAACCGCCCCCAUGAUCCAGUUACCUCCACCUGGUCCCACCCUUGACACGUGGGGAUUGCUACAAUUCAAGGUUAGAUUUGGGUGAGGACACAGAGCCAUACCAUAUCAGCCCAGAUCAAGUAGUGACAGAGUAGGGAUUUGAAUACAGGUUAUAGUCACUAUUGUGUUAUUUCUUGACUUUUGUACUAUUAAAAAACUGUAGCCAGUGAGGCUUCUACCCUUAGUACCCAGAACUCCUUUUAGGUAUAGCAAUUGUUUUUAGGUAAAUUUAUAUUGAGUUUAACACCUGUGUGAUUAAAGACAACUUUCCAAUGUAGUAUCUGUAGCCAUGUCCCCUAAUGGCUAUUAGUGUUCAUGGUUAGUGUGUUGAAGAUGAGCCAGGUACAUAACGCGGCACAUUUUCUGCAGGUCAGCAGUAAGGUUUCAAGGUACAGUUAUGGAGGAAAGAAGAAAAUGACACAUUGAUAACACAGGUCUUUAUUCCCUUUUGAAUGAGACAGUUUUUAAAAGUUGAUUUAUAAAUACAAAAAUACAUUCUCCAAAGAUAGUAUUUCCAAACUGUUAUAUACCCAUCUACUCCCAACAUGGAUAUAAGUUUUUUAAAAAAAUAGUUGUAUAUAACAUACAUAUCUGCCCCAGUGUUACUUCACAGGCCUAUGCCCUACGGGAACUCCACUCUCCCAGCCCCACUUUUUCUCUUGGUUCUCCCACAUUCUUAUUCUCCCACAUCCCUACCCACGUUUGAGCUGGAAAGGAUGUCCCUACCCUAGGCAUGAGGUAUAUUUUAUUCUGGGCACCACACAUUUGCCCCAUAGAUAACAAUACACGUGAUGAUGUCACUAGUACUACCUUUCUAGUAUUUACAUACUUAAAAGUAGUAACUAGAACAGUUAUCACUGGAACUAAGAAUUUUCCCCACAGAGGUGAACAGACCAAGAACUAAAAUUUCAGGAAACCUGUUUAAUUUCUUUUGUAUCUUUGAAAAGUUAGUUUUAUAUCUAAGAUUUCUUCACAUAGGUUAUAAUUCAUCUGUAUGUUCAAGCUUUUAUGUAAAAAUAUAUAGUGCCUUCAGUUUUAACAUAGUUUCACAUGUUCUCAGAACUGCUAAAUUCAGUGCUACCAGUAAGGCUUAAUAAGUAGUUCAUUGACCCUGUAAGAUAGGAGCACUCAGCUCUGUCACAAUUUGUUGUUAAACACAUCACUCAAUGUAAGUAUAAAAAUAUUUAUUGAUAAAAAAUAAACUUAUAAUUCAGCAACUUGAAGUUCCAGGAGCAUUUCUGUUGUUCCUAUGUCAGUAAGCCCUUGAUUUUUCACAUUAAGGAGGGAAAGCUAAGCAUGUUACUUGAAGUAAUUUUUUCCCAGUCACCAUCAUGUUGAUCCUGUGCACAACGAUAUAUGCGAGGAACUCUUAAGCUUAGUCUUUGAUUCUGACAGAGGCAUUCUAUGGACUGCUGCAUUGAAAAGGGCUUGCUGUUUUCAUCCAACACCUCUGUGUUGUGUGGUCUUGCUGUGAAAAAGAAGACAAUACCUUGUUUUCAGUUUAAGUAGGACCACUGGAGGAUGCAAUUAUCGGGACUGUUUUUAAAACCUAAAAGCACGUUUCUUUAGCUGAACUCUGAAGGGACAGUAAAGAUACAGUAUUUUAUAAAUCAAUAUUCUGCAUCAAAAAGCAUCCCAACACUUUGAGAGGCCAAGGUGGGAGGAUCGCACGAGCCCAGGAGUUUGGGACUAGCCCUGGCAACAUAGUGAGACCCUGUCUCUACCAAAAAUUUUAAAAAGCUGGGUGUGGUGGCACAUGCCUGUAGCCCUAGCUACUCAGGAGGCUGAGGUGGUAAGACUGCUUGAGUCUGGGAGGUGAAGGCUACAGUGAGCUGUGGUCGUGCCACUACACUCUAGCCUGGGUGACAGAAUGAGACCUUGUCUCAAAAAAAAUAAAAUAAUAAAAUUUAAAAAAAUCCUUCAUUUAUCUCUACUUAUGUUUAGAUAGACAACUGCAUCCUGAAAUAGGAUGGAUUUUGUUCAGGUUAAUAUUAGAAGAGACCUGCUCUGAUACUACAUACAACAGAAAGGCAGUUUGCUCCUACUACAUACAACAGAAAGGAAAACUAAGGUGGCCUCCCUAUUAAACAUUUGUUGCACAUUUGCUGAUAUUUAUAGUAUUUUAUAAGAAACUGGCAUAUAACAGCAGGGCAAGGUGGUUCACACCUGUAGUUCUAGCUACUCAGGAGGGUGAGGCAGGAGGAUUGCUUGAGCCCAGCAGUUAAAGGCUGUAGUGAUCUGAUUCUACGACUGCACUCCAGCCCGGGUGACAGAGUAAGACCCUGUCUCAAAAAAAAAAAAAAAGAAAAAAAAGAAACGGCAUACAAGGCUGGGCAUGUUGGCUCAUGCCUGUAAUCGCGCAGCACUUUGCGAGGCUGAGGCAGAAAGACUGCUUGACACCAGGAGUUUGAGACCAGCCUGGGCAACACAGCAGGCCCUGUCUCUACAAAAAAAUAAAAUGCAAAAAAAAUUGGCACAUAAAAUUAAAGACUGUCCUGACUAGUGCCUGAAAUUAUGAUGAGUUUCUUCAAGUAUGAAUAUAUAACCACCACCUGGAAGGUUCAGUAAAUGCCCUCAUCAAAUACACGCUACCUUUGCACACUUUGUAGUAUGUAAGAUACUUGUGUAUUCAGAGUAACCAAAAUAUUUAAAGGUUAUUGGAUGUUAAGAAAACAGGCUUACCUUUUAGUGUUUUAAAUUUCAUAUAGUUUCUCAAUAGUACUAUUGUCUAAUAAUCAAAAUUAUUUUAUAUUUCUAAUCUAAACAAUAUUAAGCUUUCACUAUAUUUUCUCCGUACCUUCAUAUUAAAUGCUUGAGAUUUACUCUCAACUUCACAUGUUUGUGCAUCACUUUCUUUGCAGUAACUUUCUGCCCCAACUGUAUCCAUAAUAUUGCUUCCACAAUUCUGCGUAUUAUAGCCACUAUCCAUCUGACAGGAGAAAAAAGAAAAAAAUAUAUUGUGAGGAACUUAAAAGUCAAAUAUUUAAAUAAGUAAACCACUAUAAACUCUCAUUCACUACAUCUGAAUGAUCCUAACAUGUAAUAUUGAUCAUGUUGAACAAAAUUCAAAAGUAAUGCACAAAUAUAAAAGGUAGUCCUGCAUAGUACUGAUUAUUGUAGUCAUUUUACAAUUCCUUCCAAUGAAAUAUAUCUUGUAACUUCCUUAAGAAUCAGUGAACAGCCUACUGACACAAUGCUUUCCUGUUAUUUUGUGAUCGUACCUAGUAGACAAAAAUGAGUAUUACAACUAACUUCACCUUCCAACGCAUUUUCCAGGCUUGUCUCUAAAUGGCUUGAGGCAUGCUGCCUUUAAAAAAGUGGAUUAUAUUAUAUUUACACCUAGUUGUUCACAAUAAUGCCACAUAUAUAAUGGCUCUAGAUGUUAGUUCAGCUUUUCAUGUUAAUAAAAAUUGUAGCAUCCUAAGAUACACUGUUUCAGUGCAAAAGAGCAAAAAAGAAAGAUUCUAGCGAACUUCCAGCUUGGAAACAUUUAUUGAGUGUCUAAAAAGGCCAGGCACUAUCUCUAUAUAUUUAAUAUUUUUUUCUCCUUUCAACAACCCUAAUACUUUACUAGAGAAGGAAAUUAAGGCUUAAAAAGCUUAACUUUCACAAUGUCAUCCAGUGAUGAGGUGAUGAAGAUGUGAGACCUAAGUCCAGGUUCUGUUCACUGCACAACGCUCCAUUUACCUGUAUAAUGCUGAGCACCAAAGAAAGCAAUCCACAAGGGAAUCAUUUUGCAUUUAAGCCCUCCCUGCAAGUUAGGAUCAGAGGGAAGGAAAAAGCUGACUGUCAUUUUGUUUCCCUCACAAAGGUACAGACUAGCCUAGAAACGGCACUCUUUAUCACUUAAUAAUCCUGAAAAAAUGUUCCCAGAUUUCAAGGCUGGAUACAUAUCUGCUUACUACUAGAGGUCAUGUUCCAAUUAGAACAAAAGCCUUGUGAUGUGUAACAUUUUUGGGGAAAAGCCUUGUUCUGCUAUCAUUCAAUAGCUACUUGAUCAAAAAUAUAAAUGUCAGAUUGCUCCCAGAGAUUCUGCCAAUAGCUCUUCCUUCUAAUAUUCAUCACUGCCAAAUAGCUGGCUUAUAAUGCAAUACUAAUAUGUAACUGGAUAUAUAUGGAGGGAAGAGUUACUCAUUAGUACAGCAGGAAGUAAGGCAUGCGGGGAGUUUGUCCCACACUAUGGGAAGAGCAGGAUUGAUGAGAGCCAAGUUGAGAUGGUGGCUGACUUCACUGUCUCUCAUCUAGACUUCUGCUAAUGUCAAUGCCUAAUAUGUACCAACCAGGCAACAGAUACCUUGUUAUCCCCCACAGGCAUCAAGGCAGGCAUCAAUCUCACUUUAUAGCUAAGAAGGAUGAGGGGACAAAAAUUAAAAAGUCAUGUUCUAUUCACUGCUAUGUAAAUCUUGCCUUAAGAUCCCACAGCCUGGAAAUAAAAGAACUCUAAUUCAAA